AAGCAGCCUCUGGCCCUGAAGCUACUGCUAGCAAGACUCGGGAGCUGGCUGGCGGGGGCUGAGGCCGACAGGCACGGGAGCCGGCGCGGCGUCAAGUGGAGCUCGGACGCACGGACCAGGCCCAUUUCCCUUUCAUCUACAGCAAUGUUCUUACUCCUCUCCUGCUGUAAAGCCACUCAUCUUCGAUUUCCCUGAGGACUUCUGCUCCUACAGACUCUCGACGGAGUAAAGCUUCCGAUAGAGGGGAAACAGAUUCGCUACUAGUGUUGAUAGUCAAGUUACUAAGGUUCUUUAUCAACGUCUCGGAGCAGAUUUGAGAGGCCCCUGAAUCGUCCCGGGAAUUUUCUUCGGUGAGCAUUUGUGGAGACUCUGGGAUGUAGGUUGGAUUAAACUUCUGUGAUGGGUCCAUCGGCGUCUUGACACAACACUAAGCUUCUCCUGGAUCUUUGAAACGUAGCAGAAACUGAUGACGGAGCCUCAAAUUGCUACAAGGUAGCCCGGAAAGAGCAAGAGUGAGUGUACUUCGGAUGAAGGGAAUGUGGACCCUCAGGACUAAAGCAGUGGGAGAGGCCUGGGAGGUGGGGCCUGGGGAGGGCGAGGUCUGCUCUGAAGUCACCAAGCUCCUGAUCUUAGAAGAGAUGGUGGGCGCAGGCUCUGGAGGCUCAAGCGGAGGAGGGGAAGGAGGCGAGUCCGGAAACCCUCGGCCAAUCAGAGAGGGCUGGGGCGGCGCCUGCUAGAAGGCUUAGCACUGCAGGGCUCUGGGCGGGAAGGCUAACCUGGUGCGGAGCCAGCCUGGGUCUCAGCCCCGCGUACGGCCUUUCACGAGUCUUCAAGCCUUCAGGCUUUCUUCUAGUCAAGAUGAGUGAUAAACCAGACUUGUCGGAAGUGGAGAAGUUUGACAGGUCAAAACUGAAGAAAACUAAUACUGAAGAAAAAAAUACUCUUCCCUCAAAGGAAAAAGGAGUCUCGCUCUGUCGCCAGGCUGGAGUGCAGCGACACGAUUUCGGCUCACUGCAAACUUCGCUUCCCGAGUUCAAGCAGUUCUCCUGCCUCAGCCUCCCGAGUAGCUGGGACCUCAGGCACAUCACCAAGCCAGGCUAAAUUUGGUAUUUUUAGUAAAGAUGGGGUUUCGCCAUGUUGGCCAGGAUGGUCUCGAUCUCUUGACCUCCUGAUCCGCCCACCUCGGCCUCCCAAAGUGCUGGGAUUACAGGCGUGAGCCACCACGCCCGGCACCUAGUUUUCUUAAUUGGUCACUGUCAUUUUCUUAAACUUGUGAACAAAUGAGAACCUAAAAGAGCCAAUCUUUCAAGAUGGAUCCCAGUGGCUAACUGAGCUUAAAUUUAAAAUAGAGCCAAGCUGCCACGUGUUGACUAGAGCUAACACGUGUACUACAAAUUCCCCGAAAACCCACACCUCUAUCUAACUUUGGAACUUUCAGAGCUCACCUGAAGCAACCAACCAGAGCUCACCUGUCGCUGCCAAUAAGGGCUCAGCUGUAUUGACCAACCAGAGCUCAACUGAGUCAACCAAUCAGAACUAAGUUUGAAUUGUUUAUUUGCAUAAAUUGACUGUACUGGGAACCUCGAUAGGAACUUUCUCUAUAAAAGCCAUAUCCUCUCUUUGUUCUCUGGAACUGCACUUUUGUUUUACACUGAAGUCUGCACCUCCCUGGUUUGCAAACUGUACACAGGAAUAGCCUCUUUCCUCCAAAUUCCUUUACAAAGAAUUUUUCUUCACAAUAUGAUGCGAGAGGUAGAAGACAUGCUUACAGCUGUGGAUUCAUAUCCUGAAAUCACCACGAUUACAAUAAAACGAAAAAUCAAACAAAGAAAUAAAAAGUAGACAAAAACCUCAAACUAAUUUUCUCUUCAAUUUACAAGGCUGAACAGCUAGGAGGAGACUUAUUGAUUCAGGACAGUUCACCUGCUCACAUUUUGAGCCAAUGGCUGAGGCCCAGGACUGGAGAUACUUCAUUAGUUUAGCCAGUGGAGAGUGGGGUUUGGAUGCUCUCAUUGGAUACUUCUAUCAUAAGUGAUGCAUACUCAUAGGGGUUAAGCUUUGCAUUAAAAAAGAUUGUAGACUGGGAAAUAAUAUAAUUAGACAAAUGUGAAUGACUUAGAGCAGUUAUUUCAGUUUCUAGGAAGCUUAAAAAGGGUUCAUUGAUUUAUUUGACUCAGCUAUUUCUGCACUGUGGGUUUUUGUUAUGUGUUUAAAUGAAUUCUAUAACAGAGGUAAUGUUGAAAAAAGAUUGUAUGAGGUCUGCUUGUUCCAUUAGUAAUGUUUGUCCCAGUUCGAUCCUUCUGAAUUUUUAUUUAUAGCAGUAAACUGUUUCCCUGUGUGUGCGUGUGUGUGUGUGUGUGUGGGUGGGUGUGUGUAAUGUAAUUUAAUUACUAGUAUUUCAGGUAUGAGUUUUGUAACCACAUUUAUAAAUGAGCUGCUCAUAUAUAUACAUAUACAUAUAUAUAUAUGUAUAUAUAUAUAUAUAUAUAUUUAGUAUGCUUCCUUC